GUGGUUGCUCGUAGUGAGUUGCGCUCGCUAUGUCUGGACGUGGCAAGCAGGGAGGCAAAGCCCGCGCUAAGGCCAAGACUCGCUCUUCUAGGGCCGGUCUCCAGUUCCCCGUGGGCCGAGUGCACCGCCUGCUCCGCAAAGGCAACUAUGCCGAGCGGGUCGGGGCCGGCGCGCCGGUGUAUCUGGCAGCGGUGCUGGAGUACCUGACCGCCGAGAUCCUGGAACUGGCGGGCAACGCGGCCCGCGACAACAAGAAGACCCGCAUCAUCCCGCGUCAUCUCCAACUGGCCAUCCGCAACGACGAGGAGCUCAACAAGCUGCUGGGCAAAGUCACCAUCGCACAGGGCGGUGUCCUGCCCAACAUUCAGGCCGUGCUACUGCCCAAAAAGACUGAGAGCCACCACAAGGCGAAGGGCAAGUAACUAUCUGUACUAGUUUGUGGCAGCUCAAGUAAAAUCGAGUCCAAACCAACGGCUCUUUUCAGGGCCACCCA